AGUUCAGAGAGAGGAGAGGGAGAAGGAGAGAGGGGCAGAGGGGAAGGGAGAGAGGGAGAGCACGCGAGACGGAAAGGAGCGCCUCAGAGUCUCUGAAGCACGCAAGAGAUAACCGAUUAGGAAUUUUUCGGGCAACUGUCACCCGGAUAGCUGUCAGAGAAUCAUCAUCACCGCAACUCUGACGUUUCCUACAAGAAGUUAGAGACUUAAGCAGUAUUGGCAUCGGAUGGAAAUGGUAUGCAUGCUGCUGUGGAAAAUAUCCCUGAGCUGAAGAAGUGCAACUAUGUGUUGUGUGUGCUAAAUGCCCAGAAGAACCCAGACCCAGUGGGUAAGAGAGACGAAAUGUGGAGAGAAUGACUAACGACAAAUCCGUGAAUUUGUUCUCUGGAGUUGCUAAUUUGCCAGCCCGAAGCAACACAUUUUACAAGGAGGAAACAUUUUGCUGCUUCUGAUUUCUCCCCAAACUGGUGCUACCAGAUGCAUGGCUUUCUAUGUGUUGGAACAAAUCAUUCCUAACUGCAGCAUACUGGGAAAGGGGAAAGGUUGAGGCAACUAACCGGCUGUCUCCAAAUAAGUGAUGAGAUAUAAUGCAUCCUCCAGUCCAUGCACGCUUCCUCUUGCAAUUUGUGCAUCAUUCCUCAGUGGAAACCUUUAAACCCUAAAAUCCAGGAAAAGAAAAUAAAUACAUUAUCAUGGACCUGAGGGAUUUUUACCUGUUGGCUGCUCUGAUUGCCUGUUUAAGGCUGGAUUCCGCAAUAGCUCAAGAACUUAUUUACACUAUUAGAGAGGAAUUGCCUGAAAAUGUGCCCAUAGGAAACAUACCAAAGGAUCUGAACAUUUCUCACAUCAAUGCUGCCACAGGGACCAGCGCCAGCCUUGUCUACAGACUGGUUUCUAAAGCUGGGGAUGCCCCUUUGGUGAAAGUUUCCAGCAGCACUGGGGAAAUUUUCACAACCUCCAACAGAAUAGACAGAGAAAAACUCUGUGCUGGCGCCUCAUAUGCUGAGGAGAAUGAGUGUUUCUUUGAACUUGAGGUGGUGAUCCUCCCCAAUGAUUUCUUCAGGCUGAUCAAAAUAAAAAUAAUUGUCAAGGAUACCAAUGAUAAUGCCCCCAUGUUUCCAUCUCCUGUCAUCAAUAUUUCCAUUCCAGAAAACACUUUGAUCAACAGCCGCUUUCCAAUUCCAUCAGCAACAGAUCCUGACACAGGCUUCAAUGGUGUACAGCAUUAUGAAUUGUUAAAUGGGCAGAGUGUUUUUGGACUGGAUAUCGUGGAAACUCCAGAGGGAGAGAAGUGGCCACAACUGAUUGUUCAGCAAAACUUGGAUAGAGAACAGAAAGAUACCUAUGUGAUGAAAAUCAAAGUAGAGGAUGGAGGCACUCCACAGAAAUCCAGUACGGCCAUACUGCAGGUCACAGUAAGUGAUGUAAAUGACAACAGGCCAGUGUUUAAAGAGGGUCAAGUGGAGGUGCAUAUUCCAGAGAAUGCUCCCGUAGGUACCUCUGUAAUUCAGCUCCAUGCCACUGAUGCAGAUAUAGGCAGUAAUGCUGAAAUCCGGUACAUUUUUGGUGCCCAGGUCGCCCCUGCAACCAAAAGACUCUUUGCUUUAAAUAAUACUACUGGGCUGAUUACAGUUCAGAGGUCCUUAGAUAGAGAGGAGACAGCCAUUCACAAAGUGACAGUGCUGGCUAGUGACGGCAGCUCCACUCCUGCUCGAGCAACGGUUACCAUCAAUGUCACCGAUGUAAAUGAUAACCCUCCUAAUAUAGACCUCAGGUACAUUAUAAGUCCCAUCAAUGGCACCGUGUAUUUAUCUGAGAAAGAUCCUGUCAAUACAAAGAUUGCCCUAAUUACAGUUUCAGAUAAGGACACAGAUGUGAAUGGCAAAGUGAUCUGUUUUAUUGAAAGAGAGGUCCCAUUUCAUUUGAAGGCGGUAUAUGACAACCAAUAUUUGUUAGAGACCUCUUCUUUGUUGGACUAUGAGGGCACCAAAGAAUUCAGCUUUAAAAUUGUUGCCUCUGAUUCUGGGAAGCCCAGUUUAAAUCAGACUGCCCUGGUAAGGGUUAAGCUUGAGGAUGAAAAUGACAACCCACCAAUUUUCAACCAGCCUGUAAUUGAGCUGUCAGUUUCUGAAAACAACCGACGUGGGUUAUACUUAACAACUAUUAGUGCCACAGAUGAAGACAGUGGGAAAAAUGCAGACAUUGUUUAUCAGCUUGGACCGAAUGCCUCCUUCUUUGAUCUGGACCGAAAAACAGGAGUUUUGACAGCCUCCAGAGUAUUUGACAGAGAAGAACAAGAACGAUUCAUUUUUACAGUAACUGCCAGGGACAAUGGGACCCCUCCCCUCCAAAGCCAAGCGGCUGUGAUUGUUACUGUUCUGGAUGAGAAUGACAAUAGCCCCAAGUUUACUCAUAAUCAUUUUCAAUUUUUUGUGUCUGAGAAUCUGCCAAAGUAUAGUACUGUGGGGGUAAUCACAGUGACAGAUGCAGAUGCUGGAGAGAAUAAAGCUGUGACUCUUUCCAUUCUAAAUGACAAUGAUAAUUUUGUGUUGGAUCCCUAUUCUGGAGUCAUAAAGUCAAAUGUCUCAUUUGAUAGAGAGCAGCAGAGUUCCUACACUUUUGAUGUCAAAGCCACUGAUGGAGGACAACCACCUCGUUCCUCUACUGCAAAAGUAACUAUCAACGUCAUGGAUGUCAAUGACAACAGCCCAGUUGUCAUUUCUCCACCGUCUAAUACUUCCUUUAAGUUGGUGCCCCUCUCAGCCAUUCCUGGCUCCGUGGUAGCAGAAGUUUUUGCAGUGGAUGUUGACACUGGAAUGAACGCUGAACUAAAGUAUACUAUAGUGAGUGGAAACAAUAAAGGCUUAUUCCGGAUUGAUCCAGUAACAGGUAACAUUACUCUGGAAGAAAAACCAGCACCUACUGAUGUGGGAUUGCAUCGUUUGGUGGUCAACAUAAGUGACCUGGGGUACCCUAAGUCUUUGCACACGCUUGUGCUUGUAUUCCUUUAUGUUAACGACACUGCUGGAAAUGCCUCCUAUAUCUAUGACUUGAUCCGCAGGACUAUGGAGACCCCGUUGGACAGGAACAUAGGGGAUAGUAGCCAACCCUAUCAAAAUGAGGACUAUCUAACCAUCAUGAUUGCCAUCAUCGCCGGUGCCAUGGUGGUCAUUGUUGUGAUCUUCGUCACCGUUCUGGUGCGCUGUCGCCAUGCAUCAAGGUUCAAAGCAGCUCAGAGGAGCAAGCAAGGUGCCGAAUGGAUGUCCCCAAACCAGGAGAACAAGCAAAACAAGAAAAAGAAAAGAAAGAAAAGGAAGUCUCCCAAAAGCUCUCUUUUGAACUUUGUUACUAUCGAAGAGUCCAAACCCGAUGAUGCAGUUCAUGAACCUAUCAAUGGGACAAUAAGCCUGCCGGCUGAACUGGAGGAGCAAAGUAUAGGAAGAUUUGACUGGGGCCCGGCACCUCCAACAACAUUCAAGCCUAACAGUCCUGACCUGGCCAAGCACUACAAAUCUGCUUCUCCACAGCCUGCUUUUCAUCUCAAACCAGACACUCCAGUUUCCGUGAAAAAGCACCACGUGAUUCAGGAACUCCCUUUGGACAACACCUUUGUUGGGGGUUGUGACACCCUUUCUAAACGCUCUUCCACUAGUUCAGAUCACUUCAGUGCCUCAGAGUGCAGUUCCCAAGGAGGCUUCAAGACAAAGGGCCCCUUACACACCAGACAGGUAAACGAGCACUUUUACUGGUCUAUAAGUACUGCAUACAAGUGCCCAGUCAACCAGUAUUAACGUGCCAGUAUGUCUAUUGUUUUGGUCUAACUUUAGCUUAGUUAGAAAGAGGUAAAAAAAAACUUGACCCCUUUUCUAUUCCUCUGGGGCUCAGUCAAGAAUUUUUAGAACAGCUUUGAAAUUUCUGAGUUCUGAGAAUAUUUUCUCCUUUCAGUUUCCUUCAAAUGGCAAAAGAUGAAAAGAGAAAAUUAUUCCAAAAUGUCCCAAGAUAAUGUUUGCUGAAGAAGAAAAAACCUGUCCUGAUAUGCCAAAUUCUGCUCCUGGGGGUUUCCAAAUUGACUGCUUCAAGACUUUCACCUUACCUUUUGAUCUAAAAAGUCACCUUCAAAUCUCAAGUUUUCAAUGACUUUUGAAGGUGUGACUGCAAUUAUGUUGCAGCUAUGGUUGCUAAAGGGGUUAAUUUUUUUUUUAGUCUCUAAACAGGAUAGUAGAAUAUUAAAUGUACAUCAGCUGUGAAGCACAUGAUCGUUGAUAGAUUGCAACUAAGCCAUAUAGGAAGUCUUCUCUUUGAUUUCAAAUUAUUUUAUUGUAAUAUAUUAAAUUCGGUACUUAAUAGAAAGAUUUUUAGUGUCCGCAGUGGCCAAAUACUCUUUCAAAAAAAAAAAAAAAAAGAAUGCUUGCUGCCUAAUAUAACUGAUUUAAAAAGAAAAGAAUGAAUCCAUUGUAAAUAUUCUCUCAUCUUAGUAAUGCAUAAGUGAUCUGUCAUAACUCAUUUUAAACUGUGAAAUAUGCCAUAUGAAGAGGGAUUAAGAGGCUGAGAAACUCAUAUUUCAACCAAAUCCAGAAUUAGUUUUUCUUAGGUCUAAUAAUUCCUUGUUAAUAAAGAUUUAAAUGCAGCGCUGUCUAAUUUAUUUCACUGGUGCUUGUCUGUUGCCACAAAAUUUGAAUAUCGAUAAUAGCCUGUAGAUGGCACUAGGGUAUCAUGUCGCUUGUGCUGGCCAGGUGCCAAUCCCGCAGUAGCAAGGAGAAGGGGGAGGGAAGGAUCAAGCUGGUAGUACAGCCAAAGAUACCUUUUAUUUAAUGAUAGUUGCUCUGGAGCAACUAGCAUUUAAGUUCAUUCGCUUGCUCUUUUGUGAUUAGCUCUCAGCACACCAACUUUCUAGGAUUUCGUAAUGCUAGUUCUGUCUUUGUCGAUAUGGAGUUCACCUAUGGUGAUGGCCCAUCUGUACUUGUUUAUAAAUAAGGAACACAUAGAUUUUAGAAAAUCAAGUAAAGCAAAAUUAGUUUGCAGAACAGUAUCAACAGUUAUCAUUGAUUAGUCUUUGGAGAAUCAAGAGUUUUUAUUUUCUGAGGGUGGGGUGAAGUAGGAUGUUUUAUUGAAACAGUUUCCCCCUUACCAACUAUCAUUUAUUGCUCUGGAAGGACUUAAGGCUUCAUGGUAAUAAAAUAUUUAUAAGAGUAAUUUUGACAAUGAGUCAUACAGAUACUCCCAGAACAUCAAGUAUAAUACAUAUUACCAUACAACUAAAAUCUCCAUUCUUAAAGUAAAAUAUUAAACAGUAGAGCGUUUUAAAAGUACAAAUAUUUACAGCUUAAAUACACAGGAAGAAAGGACUUUAAUCAGUAUAGAAUUUUAAAGGAGACUAUGAGAUUAUUACAUAUAAGUCAAAGUUAGAACGACUUAAUUUUUGUGUUAACUUUGUUAGUAUUUGAAAAGAGGUUGAUGUUUUAAAAUUUAAAAAAUGUUCAGUCUUAGUAAAGGUUUUUAAAAGUUAAAUAGUUAACUAUGAUAAGAAAAGUAAUUUAUGAAACUAAAUGAGUUUGAUUAAAAAGUUGCUCUUAAUGAACAGAAAGAAAAUUUUUUAAAUUAUUUACUUCUGUUAUGGUUACUCACAAUACACAUGGUAUUUUAUGAUAUGCAUAAUUAUGUUGAGAAACUAAUAUGACUUAAACUUUUUCAUGUAAAAUCUGACAUUUUCUUUCCAAAGAAAUGUACUGAUAUACUUCCAGCAUCAUCUUUUUUUCUGUCUAUACGUGGUGAUAUUAGCAUUGAUGUAUAGAUCCACUUUUUCUGACCUCCCCAAAAGUUGAACCUAUAUAUAGUGUAGUGACAUAAAUGUUAAGUGCAUUUCAGCAAAGUAUGCAAGAGAUCUUUUCUUGAGGCUUAGUCAGUCAUAAAAGUCUUUGUAUGAUGUAAUCUUUCAAAUAGGAUACUGAGUAAUUCUCUAACUGGAACUAAAGUGCGUUUUAGAAAUUUCUUGUGACCAUGUGUCACUUUGCAGUUCUCCUAUGGGUAUUCCAAUGUUCAUAUGGAACUAGGUAAUUCACUCUUAUGAUAAAGAGCUAUUAAAAUGGCUUUGCUUACACCUUUUAAAAGUUUUCAUGCUGAAAAAGAAAUAGUGUGAUGUUGGAGAAAAGAGAUAGAAGUCGGUGGAGAAGUGGUAGUGAUAUACAAAGUAAUAUGUACAUUUUUUUGGAUAAAAGAAGCAUAUUUCCUAUGAAUGAACGACAUCAAAUAUAUACUACUCUUUAAAAAUUUGUUUUCACUGAACUGUAUGAUUGCUAUCUGCAGAUGUUCUAGUUAAGCUAAAAAGUAAAAACUUUUUUAACUAGUGGCUUUUAUAUAAAAUGUGCUCCUGAAGCUACACAAUUUUGAAAGAGUAACAUUUCUUGCUACAAAAACUUUCAAAGGAAUUUAUUUAAAAAAAUACAAUCUGUGAAGAUUUUAGUUGUGUGACGACUAUUGCUCACACCAUCUUUUCAUUUUAUGCUAUUAAUUGAUAUGUGGGUAAAAUGCAAGAUUCUUGGUUAAAAGCUUACCAAACUUAAAUUUCACUCAUUUAUACUGUAUGUAUAACGAAAACAUAACGUCUGAUGUUUUCAUCAUGAAUUUGUUUGUGGUACAUCAAUUCCUAUAUUGUCUGAUAUUUUUCCCCUUGCUGUUUUCCCUUGUGUUAACCUGCAAAGAACAUAGGAAACACUGUAAAUCAUAUUCCUCAUUCACUCUAUUUUAUAAAGCUUUCAUGUGUCACUAAAUUUUUCACAGAUUAUUUCUUACAAAUUUUUGGAAGUGCGAUUAGCCUUUAUAGGUUAAGAAUUUACUUUUUUUUUUUUGGCAAAAGGUCAUGUCUCGGUAAUUAUUUGUAAAAAAAAAAAAAACAACAAAGUUUACAGCCAAAAGGUGAAGAGGAUGAAAACGACAACAUUAUCCAUUCCAACAAGGCUUUAAAUGAUAAAAUUCAUUGGUAUAUUUGCCUAAAAGAAAAAUGGUCUUGUUGACAGAUAUUGUUUUAAAAUAUGAUACUGAUUCUCCCUGUGGAAUGUCUGGGAAUCAUUUGGAGCACUACUUAAAACAUGGAUUGUUGGGUUCUACCCCAGAGGCUCUGAUUUCGUACCACUGAGGUCAGGACUGAAAAUAUACAUUGCUAACAAGUUCCUAGGUGGUACUGAUGCUGCUAGUCCAGGGCCCACACUUUGAGAACCACUACCUUAGCAUAUUGAAACAGGAAGUGUCAGCCUCUUUCCCUCUCGUAUUAUCAUAUCCAGAGAACCUGUUUUUGCACAGCCCAACUCUCAGCCCACUUAUUGACAGCUGUUUUAUUGUAGCUGGAGGCUUUACAGUAAGCUGUUUAUUGCUGUUUCCCAACCCAGUUGACAGCAUUUAGGGAAUUAAUUUCUUGGCCCCUGUGUGGUUUUUUGGGGGUGGGAAGAGGGAAGAUAAAUGAAAAUGUUAAAGUAAAAGAAAUAGUCACCCAUUUACAUUUGACAACUUCUUCAAGUAGUAAAACAGUCUGUAAGAGUUGCACUAGACAUUGGUUCUGGGUAAACUGUCAUUUAAUUUUCUAAAGGAAAUACUCAUUUUAGAGCUUUAAACAUCCUGACUUUUCACAAUCUAGAGUAUUUACUCACAUAUAUUUUUCUAUAUAUUGAGGAAUGUAUACACUGAAAAUGUGUAUGCGUGCUGUACUUAAGUGUAUACAUGUAUUUUUACAGUGUAAAGGGAAUUUCUUCUAUUCCAAACCAUUUAGAGAUACUAUAUUACAUUUAUGAUUACUUUUCAUUUUUGAAUAAUCUACUACAACCACUACUGAAAUGUUAUUAUGUUAUGUAAAAUGCGGAAGGCAGUCACAGAAUUGAUAUUUAGAACAGCUAGGGAAAAAAUGCAAUUGAAAGUGAAGGGGGCAAAUGUUAACUAAUGUGAGGCUAACCAAAAUCUUUAAGAUAUUUUCAAUUAUUAAAUUCUGGAAUAGAUAUAUAUAGUGACAGUUGAACACAGGUGACAACUGAUCCCCCAAAUGCAAAUUGUUUUUAAAAUGUUAUCGGUUGUGAUUUUUAUUUCUAUGGCUCUUUGGCUAAGUGCCCUAUGGUCAUGAAGUCAGUUUUCAUACUUAUGAGGUAGAAGAUACCCAGAGCCCUUGGAUAUUAACACAGAUUUUUGAAAUGAGGAUAGGCCACCCAUUCAAACUGGCUAUCUUUCCAUUUGGGUUUGUAAGAUAAAUAUUUGACUAUUUUUCUUUCCAUCUUGAUAUUCCUAAGCUAUAAAAUUCAAGACGCAUUUUGGCCUUCCAUUGCUAAUAACAUUAAGCAGAAUAAAAAUGAAAAGUUACUAUUGUAUUAAACAUAGACAUGUCUGUUGAUUCUUGAAUAUUUGUUAACGUAGAGAAAAUAGUAUAUGUGGUGACAAUAUUCUAUUCUCUUAUUAUUUGUUUUUGUUGCCAUUAAUUCAAGAUAUAGAAACAAGGAACAUUAAUGUUCUCCUUAGUUUCAGACCAGUCAUCCUAUGGUGAGACAGGGCAGGCUUUGGUGUCAUUGAAAUUACUUUGAAAAUAUUGUACUUGUAAUAACAUGUUACAUUCUUAUGGUGUAAACAUAUUCUUAUUAUUUAAAUAAUUGCAAGCUAUCAUUUAUCUUCUUAUGAUUUCAUACAUUAAAUUAAAAUAUGUGAAAUAGUAAAGUAGAGGGAAUUUAGAUUUAAGGAAAAGCCUCAAAUCUAAAAUCAAAUUUUCUCAUAAUUAACUAUGAUUUAUAUUGAACCUUAAGGUUUCAUUUUCAUAUUGAUGUGUGUAAAAUAUCUAUAAAUUAUACUUAUAUUAUUAGAUAUGGCAUUGUAACGCAUCCUUUUUCAUAUUACUAAUUUUACACUACAGUACUGAAGUAUGAAAAUGACACCUUUAAAUCAUUUUGUUUUCUGUAAUCUUAUUUCCACAACAAUUUUUGUUGUCUUAUUUAGAUUGUUUUUAUUUCUAAUUUUUUUUUUUCGGUUGGGGGAAUUCAGAAAUCCACCAAAUGCUGAACGUUACAGUUGUAGCCUUGGUCCCACUAUACCAGUCUGGGUGUUUACAGGGUUUCAGGGCCAAGUCAGAUGUCUGUAUUGCUCUUUUACAAUACUUCUCAGUUUGACUUUGUUAAAGGUGAACUCUUAGCUUGUAUAUAGUUAAAAACAUAACAAAACUGGAAAUCCAGUGGAUUGUUUACUACUUUGACUUAAAAUCCUUGGUGCAAUCUUUCUUUGAAUUUAGUUUGGUGUUUUCUUGAAGAUAAUUCUUUAUUAUAACUAGAAAUUACUCUCUUAAUAUUAGUAAAUCAUUUAAUAUCUUAUAUAUUUCACUGAGUUGGAAAGUACAAAUUAGUUAAUGCAGAUUUUUAAAGGUUUGGCCUUUCUGACACUCAACUUCACAUUUAAUAUUUUUUCCACAAUUUAUUACAUAUAAGGACCCUAACCAUUAUAUCAGAUUUAUUAAAAUAUGACUCUAAUCACAGGCCAGGUAUUAGUGAAAAUUUGGAAAUGCAAGUCAGGAAGAGGCUUAUUCUAAAGUUUCAUGGAGGCAUAAAAGUCAGACUCUUUCGUAAGUAAUAAUGCUAAUGUCUUAUAGACUUUGACAUAGUCAGCGACCCCCAAAUCUACAUUAUACUACAGAAGUAAAGACAAAUGUAAAAAUAGGAUCUCUCAUGUACAUAAGGAGAUGUACUCUGUUUUUAAGAUUUCAUUGGUUGUUAUUUAAGAAAACUGUCAAAUCUGUCAAACAUUUCAUUUAGAAAGGAACACAUGCUUUUUGCCUUUGUUUGAUACAAACCUAUUGGGCUGUCAGUCACCAGAAACAUAGAACAAAAAAGAUUUAUUACCAUGAUUGACAUUUUGCUUUUGAUUUAUAUUCUUUUCUUCUGUAAGCCAAGACUCAUUAAAUUUUCAAAUUCCUAAAUAAGUUAAACAACUGUCCUUUUUUAACAGUAAAGAGUGAUACAGAAAUAAACUGGAAAAACAACCCAUAUUUAAUCUUUCUCAUUCAUAUUUUUGUCCUAUAGACAGUUUGUCUCUGAUAGACAAGAAUAGUGGCAGAAUCAGUAGAAUUUUCUGAGGCAUAGCAUAUAAAUAUAAGAAAUGCAGAACUCAAAGUCAUUCAUUAGGGAUCUGUUUUUACAUAUUUAUUCAUUAUUUAAAUGGCAUAUGAAAAUAUUUUCCCUUGAUCUUUUACAGUUUGAUUGAUUAGAGUGCCAUAAGCACAUAUCACGUUUUAAAUGAUGGGCUUGAGACCACCUGUACAGCUAAGAAUGGCAAAGAUAGAAGCACAGUCAAGGUCUUUGAGGAAUAUUUGAUUGAUUCUAUCAUUUUAUACUAAUUAUUCUGGAUCCUUGAGAAAAUAUAUGAAAUGAACUUACCUGUUCUUGAAAGGAGCCUGCUACGUACAGCUUCACCACUUAGUAAUUUAUGUGGAUAUUUAAUUGUGUGGGCUGUAGGAAAGAAUGGAAAUGUGGUCAAUUUUAUCAUGUUUGUGUAAUAUCUUGUAUUUUAACAUUCUUCUAUAGUUUGUCUCUCUAUCCAACCAUCUCUGCAUUUGAGUAUUACACUGCUUUGUUAAUAACCACUCUCUGGGCCUUUUUCAGCCUGUUAGCAGUUGAUUAAGAAACACUCUAAUCCCUUUCAGGAUAUUGAGGAGCUAAUGGAUUGCAGACUAUUUGGAUCUUUAAGCUUCUAUUGUAAACGGUAUGAAGAAUUGUCAUUGAGCUGAUAUUUGCAUAUAUCUCUCCCAGUGCUAGUUACUUUGCCUCCUUUUUUGUCCUCUUAAUCUUCAGCUUUCAUUCUGAGAAUAUUUAUUUUAGUCGGAAAUAAGCAUGCCAGUGAUAGAAAUUUGGGAUUCACCUCCAGAUGAAUGCCAUCACAGACAGGGAAGCUCUGGCACAUUUUGCAUAGAUCUGUAUGAACACAGUGAACCCUUCAUAAGCUCUUAGAUUGCAGGAAAUCAGUGCUGAAAAUUAAGUGGGGUUUUAAAGAUUUGCAAAGUAGAGAGCUUUGUAUAAUGCUGGUAUUGCAGGUGCCUAUUAAAUAUGAAGUAAAGGCUUUGUAAUACAACUAGCUAACACAUUUCCCUCCACAUUAGAGUGAUUUAUAGCCUAGGGAAUUAGUCUUGCCUAUUUUUUCCAAAUGCAGAAACACUGGAUGUGACUGAAAGAAUAAAAAUCUCAAAUACAUGCCUUACAAUGGACUGAUUUGCUGUUGGAUGAUUCUAAUUAUUCAAGAUAGAUGAUGCAGGCUUGUUUGUACUUCCUUGUGGUAUCUCUGAUGCCCAUGAUCUGGCCUUCAUUUCUCCUAAGAAGAAACUCUCAAUUGUGUAUGCAGACUCUCUUCUGAACCUAAAUCAGAUUAACACCCCAGGUGUCUAUAAGACUAUAUAGCAUUACCAUAAUGAAGAGGCCUGGGUACCAAGUGAAUGCUUCCAUCCUCAUAGGAAUUACUAUUGAAUCAUUUCUCAAACUGUAUUUUUAGAAUUCAUCUUUGCUGCAUUUGUAAAUAUGGUGUGUAUUUGUAGCACAGCAUUUUGUUCUAGACAUACAUGGAUUUCAAUAUAUUUAGCUUCAUGACAAUGUUCAGUAAAAUCCCUUGCAGUUCUUUAAUACUUAAUGUCUUUGACUAGCCCUGUUAGAUAUAAAUUGGAGCAAAUAGCCAUGCAUAUUUUAAAAUGAUUUUAUAAAUCCUAUAUUUUCACCUAUUAGAAAAAGUGUGUAAUCCAUAUGCAGCCCACAGUAGGCACAGGGGCCUGUGAGAGUCAUAAUAGAUGAUUGAUUUAGAAAAGAAAACAGUUUUUGUGCAAGACAAUAGCAACUGCAAUUCAGUGAAUUAGGUUUUUUUUUUUCCUCAUUAAACAAACCUCAAUAAAGAAAAGAACGGAAACACAGAAGCAGUUAUGAAAUGAAGCUGUAUCUUUUAUAGAAGGAGAAUGUCUUCUGCUGACAGUAGUAGUUCUAUAGUAGACAUUUUCUGGAAAGAAAAAUACUGGUGGUUUUUUGGAUUCGGUGGAUGCAACCAAUCUGUGCCUCUGUGUGAUAGCAGCUGCAUGCUGAGGACUUUCAAAUACACAGCUACAUAGGAUUCGGCAGGAAACUUUUUGUAGAAGGUGCAAAUGACAAAUGGAGACAAAAUGGAGUGAGUUCUGAGUUGUGAGUUGAUGCCCUCCUGUGUCAUAUAUUCAUGUCAUUGAACCGAUUUUCACAUUGGAUGUCUAGAAUCACAAUAGCCUUCCUUCUGUGUGUCAGCUGGGAACACACCUGGACUGGCUACUUUUCUUUGCUCCAUUUCUUGUCAUUCACUAGGUGGACUAUAUUCAUGUAUGUUGUUAAUACAUCUGAUUUCUUAGUUUCUUGAUGGAUUUUAAAGUGAUGUAAUAUUAUUUCUGCAUAAUCUUUUCCGUAUAUAUAUCCAUAUAUAUAUAUAUAUAUAUAUAUGUUGCUUAAGACAACCACAAAGUGUGAAAUAAAAUCUAUGAUGUGUCCUUUCUUGCUAGAAAUAGUAAAUUCAUAUUUAUUCUGACUUAUGGUCUCAGAUAAUAUAUUUUCCUUUGCUAUUUUUUGUAUUGAGUUUUUCUUACUGAUGCCUUUUUCCAAGUUAAGGAAUAAUGUUAGAUUUAGGUAUAUAGAGUAAUAAUAUUUCAAUGCAUUCUCAACCCAUUCAAAUUUCCAACAUAAAAGAGAUGGUAGAAUUUAUACAAAAUCAUCAUUUUUUGCCUUAAAACUUAAAUAGGUAUCAAAAUUGUAUUACACCAUAGUAAAAAUUGACACAAUUUUUAGGAUAUUUUAGUAUGACAUAAACUCAUUUUCAUUCUUGGUCUUAAAUGGCAAGAUUUUCUGCCAUGCAGUGGUAGCAAAAUAUGUUGAAUUCAUUGAUUGAUUUUUAAGCAUGAUAAUAAUUAAGUAAAAGCUUCUUGACACCUAAAGUCUCUGUUUUAGACAAUUAAAUUCUGCUUUAGCUAAGGGUUAUUGACUUCUGUAUGAUACUGGGAGCAACACUCCUCAGGGUUUAAACUAUUCUUGCAGGACCAUCUGUUAUUUGCAGGGACUGUGCAUCCUCUCCAGCUGAUACUGUGUGAACCCAGGCGUAUUUCAGGAUUGUUCCUCACAUGGCCCUGGUUCCUGAUGAUCUUUUGGUCUCAAAUGGCAACUCAGUAAAUCCAAAUACUGGUAUGCCACUACUUAAAGUAUGAAAAUCUUAGAGAAUAUAAGAAAGUUCCUCAAAGUAAGAGACUGUGUCUUACUUACCUUUGUAUUUCUAACACUGAACCCACAACAGUGCUGAAAAGAGUGAACUUAGUAGGCAUUCAGUAAAUUUUGAUGCAACCUGAAGAUCAGUGAUCUUGAAAUUUUAUUUUAUAUAUAUAAGAUUUUCCACUGAUUUAAUCUUUACAACAAUCAUUCAAGAAAGACAUCAUUUAUGUUCAAAAUAUAUUCUUCCAUCACUUAGAGAUGUCUGUGGGUCCCAUUUUCUCAGUAAUUUUGGACAUAUCAUUAUGUCUGCCCAUCAUAUCAUGGUUUUUCAUAUUAGGAAAUAAUGAGAAGGCAAGAGGUGAGCUAAACAAACAGGAUCAAAUUCCUUCACUUCCAAGCCUCUUCACCCCAACCUUUUAUUUAAACCUUUCAGUACUUAGAUCAUUGAUUUAUUACUUCUAAACAUAAUGAUCAAUAUAUGUACUUUCAUAGGUGCUUGAUAGAGAUACGUGUUUGUAAGAAAAAUACCGUAUCACAUUAAAGUUUUCUUAAUAGACUUUUGAGCCAUCCAGACAGUAUGCCAGAAUCAAGUAUAAAUUCUAUAAAAAGAAGCAAAAUAAUAACUGAAUAGUGAUUAAUGCAGUGUCUAGCAACUAUAUUAAUUUUAGAAAGAUAAACUUGGUGUCUAAUAGAACUUAUAGAAUAGUUACACAUUCUCAAGUUUCCAAUGCACCUUUGGGAUUAUUUGGCCUAUUUAAUUCUUUUUCUGACUGAAGAAAUGGAGACUAGAGAACUAAUUUGAUAUUUGGAGUAACAAAAACUGACUUGAUGAACUACUACAUAAAGACUGUGAUACUGGGCACAUCAUUUAAAUGCACUAGUCCUUGCUUUCCUUGUCUGCAAAAUGGGUGUAAUCAUGCCAAAUCCAUAUAAAGUUGUCCUAAGAUUAAGUGAAUAUAUAUAUAUAUAUAUAUAUAUAUAUAUAUAUAUAUCUGGCUCGCAAUAGCCAGACACUCAGAAAAUGUUACCUGUUUUUCUACCUCCUGUCCAAGAAUACCAGCUUGCCAUUGACAGAUGUUUGCACAUUCAUUUAGUGAAUGCUUUCUUGAUUUUGUUUUUGGUUGUUUUCUUGAAUCUGAUUUCUAUUGUAUCUUUUUCACGACUCACCUGUGUUCAUCUGCUUUUGUGUUAAAACACUAUCUGGUUUCAGAUUAUUUAGGACUUUUGGAAAAUUGAUCUUCAUAACAGUAUCUCAAUAUAGCAUAUUUGAUGUUGUUUUUUAUCUUAAUCCCUGUUGUUUCACAUUUGUAUAAUUGCUUCGUCUUUCAUUUUGAGUAUUUUACCUAUUUCAUUUGCAUGUCAUGUUUUAAAAUUAUUCUGUUCCUUUUAGUGUUUGUAAUGAAUUUACGUCCCCAUAGAUUACCCAGAAGCUCCACCCAUCUGGGAAUUUUCACCGUAUCCAUCACUCCUAUUACAAAAUCACAUAUAAGAGAGAAUCUGUUUCACAGUCAGUACUUAACACAGCUGGAAUCAUUUGAAACCUGCUGGUUCUUGCUUCCAAUUAUUCCAUAGACUGGAAAGCAUCCCUGUUGAAGUAAUGGCAUCCAUGGUGUAAUCAAACCAGCUAAAAUGCCUCAAAGUAUAUGGAUCAUAUUUCUGAGAUUGAUUGAAUUCAUGGUAGAAGCAUAAUCACCAACAGCUUUUACUAUUUUUCUUAAUUUAACUUAUAUUCAUUUUAUAAGUAAGUUUUUCAUGUCUCAAUAUACAAGUUUGUAAUGUUUGAGUAUGUGAGUGACAUAAUAACAUAAAUGAGACACAACAAAUAAAAAUAUUACACACUACGGUAGUACCCCAAAAAUACCUUUUGAUAAUAUCCUGGGGCCAAAAUCAUUUCCUUUUGUUGGAACAGCUGAAACCAUCACGAUAAAGUUACUGAUUUGUAUUUAGAGCAGAAUGUAGUGGAGAUUUGUUACUAGUUCAAUUAACUUUAUCAACUAAAUAAGAAGUAGAUAUAGUCAAAUUUCAAUUGGCUUUGUUGUGAUUUUGAUUGAAUAAAUUAAAUAUGUAACUUCUUGUUGAACUUAACCACCCUCUCAGUGCAAUACAAUUGUUUUGGAUUGGUCUUUUAGUUUAGUUCUAGUUUUAUAUAAGAAGACAGUUUCAUAAGACAAGAAUUUAAAACAAAACAAACUUAAAAUUAAAAUACUCAUUCUUUGUGCUUAGAAAGCUUAAUCUAACACAUAAAACCUGGAAAACUGGUGUGAUUUUCUUUAGGCUUCUGCUUGUUUUAUGCUAAGAUGUGAUAUCCAUUUUAUAGCAUUGGGAUACCAAACAGGGCAGGGACAUAGUGUGGAUAUUAUCUUGAAUAUCAGACCUCUUAGGGUUAUUACAAGGAUUGUAGCAUGGCAUAUAGUACAUGUUUGGUAAAUUCUAUUUAAUCCCACCACAUAGGCAGACAUGGACCUAAUCAGGCAAAAUGUUAAACACAUUUUAAAUGGUUAAAAUCAGGCUUUAAGGAUUUGGAUUCAUUGUUUUAUUUGAAAUAUUUAGCAUUCUCAUGGCAUCAAGUAUGUAUACAUGUAUACUGUAUGAAGCGAUAUAUUUAUUAUAUACUGCUAAAUGUAUAUUCAAAAGGCUACCAUUUUAUGUUUUUCAUAUCAGUCGUUUCCUCUAUUAGCUUUUUUUUUUCUUUUUUUUUUUUUUUUUUUUUUUUUUUUUUUUGUGACGGAGUCUCUGUCGUCCAGGCUGGAGUGCAGUGGUGUGAUCUUGGCUCACUGCAAGCUCCGCCUCCCGGGUUCAAGCCAUUCUCCUGCCUCAGCCUCCCAAGUAGCUGGGACUACAGGCGCCCGCCACCACACCCGGCUAAUUUUUUAUAUUUUUAGUAGAGAUGGGGUUUCAUCGUGUUAGCCAGGAUGGUCUCGAUCUCCUGACCUCGUGAUCUGCCCGCCUCGGCCUCCCAAAGUGCUGAGAUUACAGGGGUGAGCCACCGCGCCUUCUAUUAGCUUUUAUAAUGGAGAGGUAACUGUCCUAGAAAGUCCAUGUAAAUUCCAGUUCAGAUAAUGAACAAUUACUUAUUCUAUGAAGACAUUUAUAUUUCCUGGACUGUACCUUUCACAUCUUUCCCUAUGUGAAUGGGUUCCCUGAAGAACUUUUUCUGCCUGCUGAGCACUUAUUUGGAGGUAAGUCUAACAAUGAGAUGAUAUCCAAACUUAUCACUAGACUACUGAACGAUAUUCUAUUUUCCCUAAUGGAUACCAAUGCUUAUUCCAGAAUUAUAUUCUAUAGUUUUAAAUUUUCAUGCUUUCAAAAGUAUCUGACAUUUAGCUGUGAAAUUUUCUGCUGCCAAAGACCUUGUCAUAUGAUCCACGGACAGAUACACAGCUAGGCUUUUUAAAUUUUGUAUUAAUUCUGUUAUUCAACACACAUCUAAUAAAUAACUGCUGUGAUCCAGGAACAGCAUUAGACAAUAGGAAAUUUUUUUUAAGAUAAAAAAAAUUGUCUUUGGUUUAAAAUAUUCCAUUAAAUUUUAAGCACAGUACUUUUUUCCCUUGGAAUUUCCUUAUUAAAAAAAAUAUGAGUUCACUCUCAAUUUUAAAUAGAUGUCAUCAUUUCCCUGAAAUAUAUUUUUUAAAGUCUCUCUCUCUCACAUUUUUUUUAACUACUGCUGGAGACUUGAUCUUUCAAUGGGGUAAUAAGAUUCUAAGAUCUAUUACUCUAAUUAUAAGAAUGCCAGGUUUAAAUUUAUCCUUUGGUUAAUUUGGAGGGAAAUGUACUUUUUCAUUCUUAAAAUCACACUCCUUCUACAGGCAAAGGUGUUAAUAAAAUAUAGUAGCAAGUAAAACUUCAUUUUUUUACUAGAUGAGAUUAGCAUAUUUGCUAUAUUAAAAAUUACUUUAAAAACAUGGCACACAUGAAUAAUGUUGAAUGAUAACCCAAGCUAAAGUAGACAGUGGUUCUCUAAAAAUGGAAUUUCACUUGUAGAGACAUCCAUUUUGAAAAGGGCUGUUUCAAGUCAUGAUAUUUUGAAAAAAUGUUUUAGCCUUCGUACGUUGAAAGGACAUGUUUACCACAGAUAUGGAACAUAGAUAUUAAAUUCUGGCUGGAAUAAAUGUUUGGUUUAAUUGGCUUCUGCCUCCAGAUGGUUCUGAUUUUAUCAAGUCCAUUUUCUUAUGAAUAUUUAUCACAGUACUUCAAGGAACCAAUGCAAUGAUAUAAACGUUGAAAACAAGAGACCUUUAUUUUAUAUAUAUAUGUUUUCCUAAAUUGAGAAACAUACAUAUCCUGAAAAUUUAGUUUUCUUUCAUCAUCGAAGAAAAUGUCAUAAUUCGGCUAUUACAGCCAAGACAGACUAUGUUUUUUUAACUCAAUUAUUUCUAAAACACUAACUUACAUAUGGAUAAAUGUUUAUAUAGGAAGGUCAUCCCCAAAUUUCAAAUUUUUAUUUAAGCCAAAAAUUUGUAUUUUAAAAAAUAAUGCAUAUAAUGCCUCACCUGCACAUUCUUGUACAAACAUAUUUUAGGAGAUAAAUCUUUAUUGCCAGAAAACAUACUAUUUUAAUUGCAAUUAGACUUCUGUGAUAACCAUCAAGCUGGUGCCUAAAUCUAAAAGGAUCUUUCCAACUGUUCUGUGGAUGCUUAGGCUUAGGCAACUAUCACCAAGUAAUUACUAUAAUUUAAAUGAACUACGAAAUUGAAACCUGCUAAAAUAUGUAGACCUCAGGAAUCAAAUGUGUAUUAACACUUGUUAAUUAAAUAUUAUUGGUUAAAAUUAAUUUAGAAAUUAUUAUUGGGUUGAUAUGACCAACCAAAAAACUAUAUGUAAAUCACUUCUUAAUACUAUGAAAAUAUGAACAGUUUGGUAAACUAAUUUAGAACCAAGCAACAGGAUAUAUUAAGCUUAGGAAGAUACAGACAUUUAAAUAAAGGUUGGUAUAGAAGUCACAUGAUAGUUGCUCUGUCUGUAGUAACCAAUUUCUAAAUAAAAUCAAAAAUGUGGCAUUCUCACCACUUUUCACAGUGACAAUUAACUUGGUGUUUUUACGUAGUUUCAAUUCCUUGCUUAUUCUGAUUUUUAUAAGUGACUAUGCAAUGUAUUACCACAUAAAAUAAAACAGUAGUGGUUAUUAAAAUCAGUACUUAAAUUUUCCCAUUUUAAAAAGUGUAGAAUACAUUAUUUUCUCUCUUUUUGGCUACAAUAAUGUCUAUUCAAAACCAUUUAUACUUUGCUAGAAUUACACUUAGCAUCUUGAGAAUUCAGUUUUCUCCUCUGAAAAUUAGAUAAUUGGACUCAACCAUUUUUUUAUUUCUAUUAUUAAAAAUUGAACUACAGCUUUUGUUAAUUACUUAGGGAAACAUUACUCCUUGGCAGGUUUUCUCUUGCCACCCAACAUCCAUCUGGCCUACUUCUUUCUAUUAUCAGUUGAUAUAUGUUCAAAUAGUGCACAUCAGUGUUAACAUUGGCUCAAGAAAAACAAUUACAAAAUAAAUCACAUGGUUCAGUCUCUCCUGACAAUGAAUGAUUUGCAAUAUUCCCAUUGUUUGUAUGAUCUAUGUUAUCACUCUCUUGCAUUAGUGUUGAUAACACAGUAUUGCCUCUAUCUUUUUUGAGGUUGCUCUGUGAUUAAUUUUCCCCUUCUGAACUAGAAAAUUAACUUUUUUCUCUUGAAUUAGAAAUCAAAAAACAGAACUACAAAACCUUGAGCAGAUUGUUGGCAUUUAUUAUUUGAUUGGAAAACCAUGAACUUAAAAUCAUUAUGUAGCUGCCAUAUUUUUAUCAGUAAUAUUACUCUUAUAAUGUUUGAUUUUAUUGUCUAUAGUAACACAUUAAGGUGACUUUAGCAUAUUUCAACUUUUGUUAAUGUUGGAGAAUUACACAUAGUUUUGCAAUAAUGUGUAAAUGUAAUAAAAAUAUCAAACAGUGGUAAUUUUGACUGAUAAUGUUAGUUAUCAGGACAAGUGUUAGAAAAGCAAAUUUAAUCAAAUGGUGCCCACUGAUUUUAUAGGCAGUUUCUUCAUUCAAAGUAAAAGUGAUGUUAAAUUGAAGAACUUGUCAGUCUCAUGCUGGAGGAAAAUCAGCUUUAGGAUUAGAAAAACCAAACUGCAAAUUAGAUGAAAUACCACAUUAAUUAGAUGAAAUACCACAUUAAUGUUAAAAAAAACCGGUGUUAUUUGGUUACAUGGAAAUAAAAUAAAACGGUUUUGCCAUCAAUGAGUCUAACACAUUUUCUUCACAACACUGCAGAAAUAAGAACCCACAGGAUGGUUCUGAAUCUUGAACAGCAGCUUAGGAAUACUUACUCGUCUAAUAACUCAAUUUGCUUGCAUUUACUACUACUUACUGCAUUGUACCCUUUCAUCUUCUAACAAGUUUAGGAAGACCAAAUUCUUUUGGUGUUUUUGAUAGAGAUAUGGUAAAGAGACUAUUUUACACUGUAGAUGGAUCGGUCUAGGAGUCACUUUGUAAGUUUGGAAAAUUGACAUCGAUGGAGGAGAUGUAUUAAAUAGUUCCAGAAAUGCCACAUUUUGGAUGCAAGACACUUUUUAAUCAUAUUAAGCAGUCUCUUUAAUGCUCACACCCUGAAUGCCUUCCUUAAAAUGUUCUAAACACUUCCAAUUUGAAGAGGGGUUAAAAUAUAAAUGUGGUAAACAAAUCACAGAAAGAAUAUACAUUCUUAAGGAAUUGUUCUUCUUAUGUUAUGGUCUUCCAAGUGCGCCAAUGACAUCGGAAGUAUGUGGUGCUAAGGUGAGGCAUUCUGUGUAAUGGCUUAGUUGCAGGACUCAAGUACUGGGAAUUCAGUCAAUUCUGCUCUUGUAAUACAUUGUGUUGGCUUUCAGAACAAUACUCCAGUGUUUUUCAGGGGAAGGUAUGAGUGUUUCCCUAAUAGAAGAGCAGAUGUUGUAGCCAAUACUGAGAGGUAGGAAAGAUAUAUAAUACUUACACAAUCUAAAAUUUCACCUAAAGUAACGUUUAAAUAAAGUUUGUUUAGUAAUCAUCAGUGUUCUGUUGUCUGUAAUGACCAACUUCACCAUAAAAUCAGAAAGGUGGCAAUGUCAACAUCACAAACAGUGGCAGCAAACAUGGUGCUGUUCUAAAUACAGAUUGUGUAUCCCAAGCCCUUUGCUUUUUUCUAUGGAUAUUCCUCCAACUACUCGUAUCAAAGAUGUAUGUUCUGGUAAAGCCUUCUGUAUUGGCAGCUCCUGCUGCUUUUCUGUCAUAUUCAAACAUGACCAACAGCAAAUGUACUUACAUUUUUUUUCAGCCAAUUCUUUCUUAUUUCUAGUGACAGUAGUAAAUUUACUUAUAGCAGUAAAGAAAAUAUGAGAAAUACUUUUCUGUAGUGCCAAAUGUUUUAAUCACUGCCUAUAUCAGCCUAAUUGUUUCCUAAUCAAAAAUUGUGAGAAUCUAAUUUUUGGUCAAAAUUGUUUAUUAUGGAGAUUUUGCACAUAUAGGAAAAAAGUGACAUAAAUAUUAUUAAUACUAAGUGACAUUAAUAUGUCAUUGGGGAAUAACCAUAUGGCUCUCUGAACAUGAUAUGCUUUCUAAGUAUUCAUCCAACAAAUAUAUGGUCAUUUGGAGGCUACUAAAAAUAAAGCCCACCAAUUUUUUAAUGUUGAUAAUGCCUCUGACAGGAAAUUUUAAGGAAUAUGAAAGUAAAACAAAAAAAUAGUUUGUGUCAAAUGAACACGCAAGGAUUUUUGCAUAAGACACACAUUAGCUAUUUAGGGCAUUAAUUGAUUGAUGAAAUAUUAGCAGUAUCUGGCAAGGUUAGAAGAUGGACAGAUAAAGAAAAUUCUGUGAGUUCAUAGAGCAUUGUCAGAGUGAGCAUUCCAGGGACAAUACAGUGUGAAUUACAGCUAUUUGAUUAAUCGAAUCAGUUCUGUAUUGUAAAAGUACAAAGAGAUGGUGUUACUGGAAUCUGAUUUGGAAUUGGAUGCUUGUAGAUUAAUAAACUGGUAUAGACUGUGCUUCCCAAUAUUUUGCCUCAAAAAAGAAUAAAUUCAUUAGGAAUUGGAACAAAAGCAAUGUUACAUAACCUUUGUAGUAUUAGAGUAGUCUAUAUAGGGAAAAAGCUAAUAAUAAAAAGUAAUCAAUUCAUUAAUCUCAAUGGUUUGCUAUUGGCAUUGAAACUAAUUAUUGAUCGCAUUGACAUGAUUAGUCAUAGCUUUAUUACUAGAAAUGUGAACAUGAUUUUAAACAUAUGUAAAACUAACUGGCCAAAAUAAUCCACAGUUAAUUUCAGCUAAAUAGCUAACAAUUUCACAGGAAAAGUGGAAGAUAUUUGAGGCUUUGUAAAGAGAAGAUCACAGCAUUCACCUUGGUACCAUUAUCUUUUGAUUUCUAGAAACACAGUUUGCAAUGCCUUGAAAGUAGAUGUCAAACACCAGCUAAUGAUAAUAACUGAUAUUUAUUAAGUACUCCAUGUGCGUGAAGUUCCUCUCAGCACUUUACAUGUAUUAAUUCAAAUAGAACCAACUACUUUCUGAGGAGGAUACUGUUAUUAUUGUCCGUAUUUUACAGCUGAGGAGAAGUUGAAUGAUUUGCUUCAGGUCACAGUUCUAGUCAGGGGAGAAUAGUUUACGGUUCCAACCCUAGCAGUCUUAGACACUGCGCUCUCUUAGCUGCUAAUUAAUACUGUCUCUAUCAUGGAACUUUUAUACAAAACAUAAACUUGUAGUUAGUCAGCAAAAGUAAAUUUUGCCAAAAAGAAAUUUGGCCAUUUUAACCUUUUUUUAAAGGUUAAAAAAAAAAUCACCGAAGUCUAAUUUAACCUUUUUUUUUUUUUUGCUUCAUUAUUAUACAAAUUUUGCCACUGAGCACAUAGCAUUAUGACAGAACUAUUCCUGAGACAUGGGGAGAUACUUUACAGUUUACAAUGAACAUUCACAGACAGUAUAUGUGAAAAGUAGAAAUUAGCAUUUGUAUCUUUUAGGCAGUACGAUUCGAGAUAUUUUUCACAAACGUGAAUUUUAGUUGUUAAUUUAAAUAAAUUUGCUCAUCUCAAAGCAGAGUUUUGUGAUUAUUCUUAUUUUAUACAAUGCCUCAUAUCAGAUAAGAAAAGAUCUAGAAGAGGGGAAAGUCAAACUCUAAUGAUAACAAGUGUAUCUCAGUCCUAGACUACUUGACUGGAAUGAUGCUUUCCUUUCUUUUUAAAUCUUUAUUCCAGCCCCUGUGCCUGAAUGGUUCAGAAGCAACCACCAGGCAUCUCUGCACAAAUUUGCCAGCUAAGAUCAGUAUAGGCCCUCCUCCAACUUAUCUGCAAUGCACUGGGAGAAUAUAUCUUCAUAUCUAUUUAGAAACAUGCAUAUAAGUUAUUUUAAUACUAUUUAUACAAUUUUAGCAUUUUCCUAGAGUAGGUUUUCCACUUUCAUCACCCACAGCUACAAAAUUAUUCAGUUAUUUUCUACAGUUUUACAAAUAUACCAUAUUACGGGCUGCUUAAUAUCUUCCUUGUUUAAGACUUUAACAGUAUCAGCCGGGCGUGGUGGCUCACGCUUGUAAUCCCAGCUCUUUGGGAGGCGGGCAGAUCAUGAGCUCAGGAGUUCGAGACCAGCCUGGCCAAUAUGGUGAAACCCUGUCUCUACUAAAAAUACAAAAAUUAGUUGGGCGUGGUGGUGCGCGCCUGUAGUCCCAGCUACUCGGGAGACUGAGGCAGAAGAAUCGCUUGAAUCCAGGAGGCAGAGCUUGCAGUGAGCCGAGAUCAUGCCACUGCACUCCAGCCUGGGCAACAGAGUGAGACUCUGUCUCAAAACAAGCAAACAAAAAAAAAAACUUUAACAGUAUUUUGUAAAUGCCAGUGUGGUGGCUUACACCUUUAAUCCCAGCACUUUGUGAGGCCGAGGCGGAUGGAUCACUUGAGUUCAGGAGUUUGAGAGCUGCCUAGACAACAUAGCGAGACCCCAUCUCUACAAAAAAUACAAAAAAUAUCCAGGCGUGGUGACGCCUUGGCACUAGAGCAAGACCCUGUCUAAAACAUAAAUAAGUACAUAAAUAAAAAUAAAAUUCAUCAACCGCGUGUUGAAUUCUCAAGAUUCCCCUUAAACCUGAGAACUGGAGAGAGCCAUUUCAGUUAUAUAGUAAAAUUAAAUUUGUUUAUCAUGGAUUAUUAUAAUGGACGUAUAUUGAUAAAAUGUCUAGGUGAGAAUUUUACAGUUGUAAUUGGAGGUCCAUUUAAAGGUUAAAAUGAAAUAGAGAGUUAUGGAUGCACAGCUUUCCAUAUUGUGUUUGGCAAAGGAAAUUGAUUCUCGGAAUGAUAUGCUACCCUUUUUGUCCACUAUGUGUAGUGCAUAUGGAUGAUGGAAUCACUUUCAUGAGUACAGUUCUUAUUUAGAACACACAUUCCGUAAUAUCCCUAGAAAAUAAAAAAGAUUUAUGUGUUCAAAAGGAGUUUCUUGAUAUGAGACAAGCAGACUGACUUUCAAUUACAAACACUUAGAAUUCUGAACCUUGCAUUUUUAUUGCGAGAACUCAGUUAUUUUCCAAAGCUUGGUUUGAGAGCUAUUUUCAGGCAGCAGCUUUUUCUUGAAGUCCCUUACUGAUAAGUAUAGUAAGCAGAAAUAUUUCAAUUACUCUAAUUAAAAAGCAGUAUUCAACAUGUUGACUGAAGGUGGAGUUUAUGUUGUUCACCAGACAAUGAGAAAUUGGGAAGGGACUAUUUUAGAUAGAUCAUUGAUGUGAGAAAGUUAAAUUCACCUGUUAAUUUGUCAAUAAACUAGAACAGCAGGGUUUCCUUUGUUAAAAUAUAAGAUAAUAUAUUGGAAACGCAUAAUUCUUAGACAUGAACUCAAAGACAUGCAGGCAGGUUUACUUUUAGCUCAUGGCAUAUGCAAAGAUAGGCAUCAAUUUGUGGUGAGGAUAUGAGGAAGUUUUUAUCUGUACAUUUGUUUAAAGAGUCAUGUUUAGAGAAGCAUUUUUUAAUAGAUACUCUUUUCAAUGGAACUCAUAUUUAAUUAGACCAAACAUAAAAGCCAACACUUUAAGUAAUCUCUUUUUAGCAGAUUUUCAUGGAAGAGUGCCAAAUUGUUUUGGUUUCACUAUAGGUUUACAGUCUUCUGAUAGAAUUCCCAGUUGGGAUUUGAAAACCAAACUGUGUCAUACAGACAUGAAUACAGUGGCCUAACGUGAUGUGUUGAAUUAGCUUUCUAGAUGACUUAAAGUAUAGCUGGGGUUUUCCUUUAUCCAGGGACUAACAUUCAAGGUUUUGUGAAAAAGAAAAUUAAUUUUGCAUUGACAUUCUGGAUGUUGGUGAUAAUUUGUAGUGACAUUAUGCCUAUUGGUUGUGAUUGUGACAGGCAGGCAGACUGGAUCCAAAUGGACAUUACAAGAGCCAAAUUAAAUAGUCUGAGCAUUGGAAAUUUCUGCCUUAAGGAAAGCAGAAGCUUUUCAGCAUGCACUUGUUUUCUACCUCCACAAUUAUGGAUUAAUAUACAUCAAUUCUAGGCAGUUGAGGAAUGACAUGAGAGGAUUAAUGGAACUGGACAACAUUACACAAGUGAAGUGAAAAUUCUGUAAUGAUUUUUCUGAGGUGAUGUAGUAGACAAGGCAAAUGGGCAUCAGCUCCUAGACUUUGCACCUUUAGAAUUUCAAGAAAAUGAUUGAAAAGAGAAAUGGAAAACAACUAUCUAACUAAAGCUGGCAUAAUAAUUUUUCUCAUCAAAUAUAUACAUCAUUUUUCACAAAUAAGGAGGAGUUAUUCAACUGAGUAAGCCAGUACUGUGUGCAGUGUAUGAUUUUAUCCAAAAAUUGUGGCCACUUUUAUCUCUUAAAACUGUUUAGAGAAAAAUUGUGCUUAGUGUGUAUCCACAAUAAGAAAAACAGAUUAGAUGCAAAAAUAAAUAUACAUAACCAGCCUUAUAUGUAAUCAUACUCAUUUUGCUUUAUGAAAUAUCUCUGAGGGGAAAAUAUUUUUUCCAUGUCUUUUUGAAGUUUUAAUAAGAUUUUUUAACCCCAAUAUAUUGAGCUGCCCUAAUGCCUACUAUUUAUUUUUUUCUCUUCUACAAAGUUUACCUAUCAUAUCAUAUUUAUGGCAACAUUUUCUACUACUAAGACUGUGGCGGUUUUUUUCCAAGUUAUCUGAAAACUUGACUGUCAUUAUUGCAAAUUGAUUAUUUCCAUAAAGGUGCUUUAAUAAAAUUUCUGUUCUUAGACUUUAAUUUGGUAAGCUCUUACACAUAUUUAUACAUAAUUUGUGAUAGGAGUUUUAAUCUUUAGAUUUUUACAAUGUGAUUUUCUCAUAUCUAUUCAUUGGAAGAGGUAGACUUCUUUUCUUUAAUUGCAUGCAUUUUAUCCUUUAACCACAAAAUGUGUUUAAAAGCUAUGCAAGAAUUAGCAAAAGUAAACUACAGCAAUAUUAAAAUGACUUAUUUGGUAUCACCUUUACAGACCCAGCUCACUUAGGCAAUGGUAUUCUAGUAAAUUACAAUAUUUUUUAAAGCAUAGUUUUUUUUGUUACCUCUUGAAAUAGUGAUUUUAAAGCCAAAAGGGUCAAGAGUAUGCCAAAUUUAAGAUGAUUAUUUGGAAAAGAGAGAUAUCAGCAACUUAAGUAUGCUGUAUUUAAGGUGAUUGUAAAAGAGUUUUUUUAUAUACAGGACAGCAUUAAAACAGAAUUACAAAGUCUAUUAACCAUAAUGAAGGAGUUCAAGAUGCAGAUAAAAUUAAAUGAUUGUCUUUAAGCUUUCAAUAAAUUUGUUAGCCAAUUUAAGAAUAAUUGCAGCUUAUGAAAGCUUGUUUAUAUUUAUCUAAUUUCAAAAAUUAAGAAAGAAUUAAAGGAUAUUUGAAGUUCUUAUUAUGUAGUUUCUAACAUUGUGAGAGAAUGGUCAAAAGACUGCUAUGUCUUAUUUAGUGUAAAUGUGUACAUACUUUACAGUUAAAGGAAUUACUGCUUUGCUACCAUCAAGGUCUUAAAACCCUGUAUCAAAACAACCUAGAGAUUUGCUUCAUUAACUCCUGUUCAUUUCGCAGGGCAAGAAAUAAGAUCCUCUUUGGCAAUCACGUGUUACCUGAAUUAUAUUUAAUCUCUUUAUUACCUUGGAAAUAUACCAAGACACUCACAUAUUCACAUACACACAGCACACACACAUACAACCCUGAUGCAAAUAUGGACAAAAUGAACACCCUCACUUAUACAUCAGUCCAUUUCUUCCUCUCAUAAAUUGAAUGUGAAUAGCUCUGAUGGCAUUUCUCUCUGACUGAAAAAUAAGGUGCCAUGCUUACUCCAUGCAAAACCCCUGUUUUACAGUUUUAUGCCCCUCACUAAAAAUAGAUAAAUCUGCAUUUGUAUGUGUCCUCUACUCAGCCUCCCUCAUGCCGCCUGACUUCUUGCAGAAGGUGUAUAUGCUUUUCAUUCUGACCAAUAAGAGGCAACUUGGUGAGUUAUAGAGAUUGACUGGGUGCUUGACAUGUGGUGCUGCUCCAUUAAAACAGUGGGCAGUUGGUACUGGGGAGGUUUAGGAGAAUUUAAGUUGUCUUUAUUGUUAUUAGAUGUGCUCUUAGAUGUGGUAAUAUUCUAAUAUUCUAUUAAAAAAUAUAAAAAUGCAACUUCAGUUCACAUUAUAAUAGGUUUUCUCAUAUUGCUUUUGUGGUCCAGAUGUGAAACAUAACAAUAAUAAUAUGUAAUUCUAUAAUCAUCUUCUAAUGUUACCAGGUAAUUUUUGUAGACAGAGCCAGAUAACCCUAUUGCUCAUUAUUUAAGUGCAAAGUACAUUUUUUCAAUCAUUAUUGCCUAAGAAAUUUUUAGGAGAUGAUGGUUGAAUGGUCCUUCUCCUCACCUCACCACACCAAGAUAGGUUGGUAUGUGUGUUUGUGUUUCCUUGCUUUCACUUUUUAAAGGAUCCUAUAGAAAAUAACAGUAUUGUUUCCAUUUAAAAAAAAAACUUGAUAAUUUAUAUUCCAUUUUAUUUCUGAAAAAUAGCCACAUUUUUACAUACCCCAAAUAAAUCGCCAUGUGUAACUAUGUGCAAAAAAUAAUUGAAUGUGGCUGAAAACGAUCUCACUUGUUGUACUAUAAUGUAUGAAUAAUAAUAAAUGUAAAACCCUUGAAAUCACAUUUUCUUAUAAUACUAUUCUAUAGGUAACACUUACAGUACAGUAUAUUAAAUUGGUACUUUGUGAAAUGAAUUCUUGAGAUACUUAGGCACUACACAAAGCAUUAUUAUUAAAGAAUUAUAGGGGAAAUUUUCCCAAUUGAAAAUUGAUAAUUAAAGGUAUUUAAAUUAUGUAUGUUGCAGAGCAGGUAAGAAGUUCAAUGUAGCAAUAUAUUUCUAUUUUGAUUUCAAAUUAAGUUUUAAUUACACAAAAAAUUGGCUCAAGAACUAGGUGAUACAUUUUAGAAAAUUUUAAAUAGCCAAAAUAAUGUUGAAAUAUGUUAUAUGGAUAAUUUAUCAAUAAAAAUUAUUACUGUUAAAAAUUGGUAGAAUUCUUUCCUCCCUGUGAUAAAUGAUUUAAGUUGAAUGGGAAUUUAAGUAACAUACAGGGAUGCAUCUUAAUACCUAUAUUUGCUCAACAGUGGUAAACACACAAUUAAAACUUGUCCUCAUUAAAAUGGACUUUUGUACACUAUAAUUUGAAGUAAGUAAUGAAUAUAUAAAGUAUUUAAAGAGUUGUAUAUCAAAAUGUAUAACGUUCCAUUUUUGGCUAUAUUUUGUAAAACAUUUUUGGUGUAAUCAGUAUGACUAUCACAUAUGUCAAAUCAAGUAUUCUACUAUUUAUUUAAACGGAUAUAUACCUAAUGUAUUUGAAAGCUUAUUGCACUCAUAAAAUUGUAUAUAUUGUGGCUUCAAAAGUCUGUACUUAUUCUUGCUUUAAAAAAGUAGUAUGUGCAUUUCUUUCCAAUUUAUUUUUAAUUAAUUAUAUUAAGGAUAACAUUCUUUACUAAAUGUACCUUAAAAUUCACAAUAAAGUUUCAGAAAUUGUUUUGUA